GUUGCAGCAGAGGCGGCGGCGACGCUGAGACACCGCAGCUUCCCUGAGCGCCGAGUCCCUCCGGGGACAGCAGCAGGGAGCGCCCGCGCAGCCACCGAGCCUCUGCCCAGCCAAGCCGCCGUCGCCGCGCCGGGGGACCGCCAGCCAUGGCCGCGCCGGGGGAUCCGCAGGACGAGCUGCUGCCGCUGGCCGGCCCCGGGUCCCAGUGGCUCAGGCACCGGGGGGAGGGGGAGAACGAAGCGGUGACGCCGAAAGGGGCCACGCCGGCGCCGCAGGCUGGGGAGCCCAGCCCGGGGUUGGGCGCCAGGGCCCGGGAAGCGGCGUCGCGGGAAGCCGGCUCGGGCCCCGCCCGGCAGUCGCCCGUUGCCAUGGAAACUGCAUCCACAGGUGUGGCAGGUGUUUCCAGUGCCAUGGACCACACCUUCUCAACAACAUCAAAAGAUGGGGAAGGAUCGUGUUACACAUCUCUCAUUUCUGACAUCUGCUAUCCACCUCAGGAGGAUUCUACAUAUUUUACUGGAAUUCUUCAGAAGGAAAAUGGCCACGUCACCAUUUCAGAGAGCCCUGAGGAGCUGGGUACACCCGGCCCCUCCUUACCAGAUGUGCCUGGGAUAGAGUCUCGUGGCUUAUUUAGUUCUGAUUCUGGAAUAGAGAUGACUCCUGCAGAGUCCACGGAAGUGAACAAGAUCUUAGCAGACCCUCUGGACCAGAUGAAAGCAGAGGCCUAUAAAUACAUUGACAUAACCAGACCCGAGGAGGUGAAGCACCAAGAACAACAUCACCCCGAGCUGGAAGAUAAAGACUUGGACUUUAAGAAUAAAGACACUGACAUCUCAAUUAAACCUGAAGGAGUCCGUGAACCUGACAAACCAGCUCCUGUGGAGGGAAAAAUCAUCAAGGACCAUUUAUUGGAAGAAUCCACAUUUGCUCCAUACAUAGAUGAUCUCUCUGAAGAACAGCGCAGGGCUCCUCAGAUCACCACCCCUGUCAAAAUCACACUGACGGAAAUAGAACCUUCUGUUGAAACCACUACCCAAGAGAAGACCCCUGAGAAGCAAGAUAUAUGUCUAAAGCCAAGUCCUGACACAGUCCCCACUGUCACUGUCUCGGAGCCUGAAGACGACAGCCCAGGAUCUAUCACCCCUCCAUCUUCUGGAACAGAACCAUCUGCUGCAGAAUCCCAGGGGAAAGGCAGCAUCUCCGAGGAUGAGCUGAUCACCGCCAUCAAAGAAGCAAAGGGAUUAUCGUAUGAAACCGCCGAGAACCCACGGCCGGUGGGCCAGCUGGCCGACAGGCCCGAGGUCAAGGCCAGGUCCGGACCGCCAACCAUCCCCAGCCCCCUGGACCACGAGGCCAGCAGCGCGGAGUCGGGGGACUCAGAGAUCGAGCUGGUGUCCGAGGACCCCAUGGCCGCGGAGGACGCGCUGCCCUCAGGCUAUGUGAGCUUUGGCCACGUGGGCGGCCCGCCGCCCUCGCCCGCCUCGCCAUCCAUCCAGUACAGCAUCCUGAGGGAGGAGCGCGAGGCCGAGCUGGACAGCGAGCUCAUCAUCGAGUCGUGCGACGCCUCCUCGGCCUCGGAGGAGAGCCCCAAGCGGGAGCAGGACUCACCCCCGAUGAAGCCCAGCGCCCUGGAUGCCAUCCGGGAGGAGACUGGCGUCCGGGCCGAGGAGCGUGCGCCAAGCCGGCGGGGCCUGGCCGAGCCGGGUUCCUUCCUCGACUACCCCUCAACUGAGCCCCAGCCUGGCCCCGAGCUGCCCCCUGGAGACGGAGCCCUGGAGCCUGAGACGCCCAUGUUGCCACGGAAGCCUGAAGAAGACUCGAGUUCCAACCAAAGUCCUGCGGCCACAAAGGGCCCUGGGCCUCUAGGUCCUGGCGCCCCGCCCCCACUGCUGUUUCUCAAUAAGCAAAAAGACAUUAUACGUGUACAAGAGAUUCUUCCCCAAAAAUCGUUCACCGCACCUGAUUGCAGUUGUCUUAUGGAAUUCAAGAAAGGAAUUAGAGUCACAUGACUAAGUGAGGUCCUGCUCAUUCUAUUUUUGUUAAUGGGUGAAGUUAGAGAACUUCUACCCUGUUCCUGGGGAGAGAACACUCAGGUAGGACUUUAAAACAAACCCUAACAACUGUAUUCAAGGUCCCCUCCCACCCAUCUCUUCUACUUUUCUUUCCUUUAGAAGUGCUUUCUUUGCCUUUUCCUUUUGGAGAUAAGUGAUUUCAAGGGUGCGCCCUCUUUCCUGUGUCUAUGCUAACUUCAAUGAUGUUAGCGGCAGUUAAAGUGCUUCAUAUAAAAAUAGAGGACAAAAUCUUUCUCGUUAUUUUAAAUUGGAAGCUAGCUGCUAAAUUCUUUAAAAUUAACACAUUGGAAUAGAAUAGAGGAAUCUAGAGGACUGAAAUAAAAAGAUACAUAGUUGCUGUGGCUCAGACAUGUGGCAUGGUGUGGGGGCUGAUAUAAUUGACUCUUGACUUCCCAAAUAGCUCUUCUUAAAGAGCUGAAAGCAUAUUUAGUGUGUGUGAUAGGGAAGAUACUUGAAGACAAAUUUAACGGUGGGAAUGUGUUUGUUGGGUCAAUCUUAAAACCAUUUUGGGUUUUUUUGCUACUAUCCUGACAUAGUAAGAAAAGACGCUGCAGCUUGCAGGGAACCACAGGAAAAAGUAUUAACAUGAACAACCUUCAGCCCCUUGGGGCCCCAAAACAGUCAAGCUUGAGUCAUGCUGAGCAUGUGUUCAUGUCACUGUACUGUAACAGGCAUGUGUCUCCAUUUUAUCCCCUAACUAAUGUUCCUGAGAUAGUCACCGUGUGCACGGUGCUGUUCAAAUAUGUUUAUUCUCAAAAGUAGAUAAAUCUGAGGGCUAAAGAGAAAAGGGAACUUUGCAGGCCUAUUGAGAGACAAGGACAACAGCUGGGACUGACUGACCAGACACCUGAUGAAGAGCUGAGGAGAUGGAAAACUGCAGCUGUGAAUGCAAAGGCUUCAGAGUAUCUUUUAUGGCCAAUUUUGUGUCAUUUGAAUCUCUGUACAAGUUGCCCCAUAUGGCUUGGACCCUGUGCUGCCAAGUUUAGAAGGUAGAGAGGAGGGUGUGGCAGUCUUUUCAAAAGAUGAGGGCGUGCCAAGGUGAAUAAUCUCCACUCUCUUCUGCACGGAGGGGUCCUUUGAAAUCUAGUCUCCCACUGAAACUCACUGCUCCACUGCACUAUCUAUGAAGAGUCUAAAAGGCCAUUCUGAGGCAGCCAAGAACUGGAGGUCCUGAGCAGGUGAUUCAGCAAUGCCAGCAGGCAAUUUGAGCUCUGAGGUUCUUUUUGGUCUCACUUGCUCUGUCUCAGCAGGUGAGAAAGGAUCAGCGCUGCCCAGCCUUCCCCAGGCUGUUUUUUUUUUUUUUCGUCUGACACAGAGUUUCACUUUUGUUGCCCAGGCUGGAGUGCAAUGGCGUGAUCUUGGCUCACUGAACCUGACCUUAGGCGAUCCGCCUGCCUUGGCCUCCCAAAGUGCUGGGAUUACAGGCGUGAGCCACCACGCCCAGCCCCAGGCUGUUCUUAAUCACUGUUUGUGGACAGCAGGUUUGUGCUCAUGCCAAGCUUGACUCCUGGCAACAGUGAGGUCCGGUCAGCUUCUGUGGUUUCCUGCUCUUGUCCACUGAAGCUUCUGGCAGUAUGCAUGCAUUAAUUUUAUGCAUUCACAAGUAUCCAGGGGAUGAGCCAUCCUGCUGAUGCUGGACAGAGUUUCAGAAGUGCCUAGAAAUAUUUAGAAUAAUAUUUAGGAUAAGGUUUGACAGAUAUUUGAUGGCAUCAUUGCAUGUACCAUGGAGGAGCACCAGGGUAACUGGUGCACGUGCUCUAACAAGGCCUAGUUUUGGAGCUUUCUCACCUUUCAGAGACCUCUGCAGUUAUUGCACUGGAGACAAAACGCAGUUCUUUCUUCAUGCUUCAGUUUUCCUCCUUGUAUGCCCCUGAGCUCUUGCCGCCCUGUAUUUCUGCUCCCCUACACCUUCUAGGAUGACCUGUUAUAAACAUUAGAUUCUAAAGCAGGUAGAUAUGUUUUCCUUUCUACAAGAUUAGCCGUAACUGUUAGGAAUGUCCAAGUAAAAA